GGAGGAGACCCGGGGAAGUGAGAGUCGGGGAUCAGUCCUGCAAGCUACGGAGUCACUACAGGGAGAGGUCUCAUCACUAGAAAUAGCCGAAGAACCUGCAGCCUCAACCAGCGUUAAGGAGGACGUGCCGUUUCUAGGGAGUCUUAGUCGGGGCUCACCAGCUUCCUGCAUUUUCUGACCGGCUCCAGGAAUAGAACCAAAAGAAGCUGAACAAGGAAGCAGCGCGGCACCAAGAAAAGCAGAAGUCGGGGCCUUGGAGGCGUGACUUUCCCCUCGGGUCCAGGAUGUUUUGCUCUGAGCAAAUGCAGGACCGUGGCGGGCCCCGUGGGGGGAUCCCUGAGUGUGCAGUGUCCCUAUGAGAAGGAACACAGGACCCUCAACAAAUACUGGUGCAGACCACCACAGAUUUUCCUAUGUGACAAGAUUGUGGAGACCAAAGGGUCAGCAGGAAAAAGGAACGGCCGAGUGUCCAUCAGGGACAGUCCUGCAAACCUCAGCUUCACAGUGACCCUGGAGAAUCUCACAGAGGAGGAUGCAGGCACCUACUGGUGUGGGGUGGAUACACCAUGGCUCCGAGACUUUCAUGAUCCCGUUGUCGAGGUUGAGGUGUCCGUGUUCCCGGCAUCAACGUCAAUGACACCUGCAAGUAUCACUGCGGCCAAGACCUCAACAAUCACAACUGCAUUUCCACCUGUAUCAUCCACUACCCUGUUUGCAGUGGGUGCCACCCACAGUGCCAGCAUCCAGGAGGAAACUGAGGAGGUGGUGAACUCACAGCUCCCGCUGCUCCUCUCCCUGCUGGCAUUGUUGCUGCUUCUGUUGGUGGGGGCCUCCCUGCUAGCCUGGAGGAUGUUUCAGAAAUGGAUCAAAGCUGGUGACCAUUCAGAGCUGUCCCAGAACCCCAAGCAGGCUGCCACGCAGAGUGAGCUGCACUACGCAAAUCUGGAGCUGCUGAUGUGGCCUCUGCAGGAAAAGCCAGCACCACCAAGGGAGGUGGAGGUGGAAUACAGCACUGUGGCCUCCCCCAGGGAAGAACUUCACUAUGCCUCGGUGGUGUUUGAUUCUAACACCAACAGGAUAGCUGCUCAGAGGCCUCGGGAGGAGGAACCAGAUUCAGAUUACAGUGUGAUAAGGAAGACAUAGGCUUUUGUCCUGCCUCGCCAUCGGAGCUCUCAUGGGCCCCAGGAAGUCCAGGGACAGCUCCCUUAUACCUGGCCCACGUCCUUCUCAGCCUGCCCUCGACAACAGUGACCAACAGACAGGCAGCUGGGUUUCCCAGGCCAUCCCUCUGUUGCCAUCAGCUUGAUUGGCUUCCCCGAGGGCCAGCAGGGCUGGGGGCUCCGGAGAGCAGCAGGAAGCACUCCCAGCCACCAGUGCCUGUCACCUCUUUCCCCUUUGCCCCUGCUUCAUCCCAGCUCUGUGUGUGGAGGACAAAGCUUCUUCCUGCGUGGCUCCAGGAAAAGAUGUGGCUCACGUAGGUGGCACCUGCCAAUAGCUUUGUCAAUCACAGCCCCAUAGGAACGUCUGGAAUUGCUUGGGAGUUGGGGAGAACUGUCAAGAAGAGUGAAGAGAGUGCCAAAGCGGAGAUCUGUUCACCUGGGGGCCAUGGAGGGGGGACCCACUAAAGAUCAAGAUCAAAGAUUCUCCCCAUCUCACAGACAAGGAAACUGAGGCCAGAGGGAGGAGAGAAUUGCUCAUGGCUCCAGAACUGGUGGCAAGUUUCUCUGGACUCUUAGGUUUAUUUUUAAUAUGAAAUAUAAAAACAGUUUCAAAUAUCUUAUUGAGGGAGAAGUAAAAACUUAUUUAAACAAUGCC